GCAGGCAAACCUGAGGUCCUCAGAAUGGCGGGCACAGGUUUGGUGGCUGGAGAGGUUGUGGUGGAUGCGCUGCCGUAUUUUGAUCAAGGUUAUGAAGCCCCUGGUGUGCGGGAAGCGGCUGCAGCGCUGGUGGAGGAGGAAACUCGCAGAUACCGACCUACUAAGAACUACCUGAGCUACCUGACAGCCCCGGAUUAUUCUGCCUUUGAAACUGACAUAAUGAGAAAUGAAUUUGAAAGACUGGCUGCUCGACAACCAAUUGAAUUGCUCAGUAUGAAACGAUAUGAGCUUCCAGCCCCCUCCUCUGGUCAAAAAAAUGACAUUACUGCAUGGCAAGAAUGUGUAAACAAUUCUAUGGCCCAGUUAGAGCAUCAAGCAGUUAGAAUUGAGAAUCUGGAACUAAUGUCACAGCAUGGAUGUAAUGCCUGGAAAGUAUACAAUGAAAAUCUAGUUCAUAUGAUUGAACACGCACAGAAGGAACUUCAGAAGUUAAGAAAACAUAUUCAAGAUUUAAACUGGCAGAGAAAGAACAUGCAACUCACAGCUGGAUCUAAAUUGAGAGAAAUGGAGUCAAAUUGGGUAUCCCUGGUCAGUAAGAAUUAUGAGAUUGAACGGACUAUUGUUCAGCUAGAAAAUGAAAUCUAUCAAAUUAAGCAGCAACAUGGAGAGGCAAACAAAGAAAACAUCCGGCAAGACUUCUGAAAAGACAAUUUAGCAGGUAGAAGAAAAGUUGGGCUUUCACAAAAGGCAUCUGAACUUUUAAUGAACUUUGAAGGACAACAGCAUCUUCCCAAAACCAUUGAUGUUUAAGUGUUUAGAAAUCAUAGAAGGUGUAGGCUGCUGUGGUAAUUCUAUUUGUAUAUCUCAACAGAAUUAAAAUGUCUAGCUUGGUGGUAUUUUUAUAGCCAUAAAAGAAAAUCUUUAGGCUUUCAAAAUAAGGAUGACUUUAGAAUAAUAUUGUGUCAUAGAAUUAAUUUUCAGCCAUGUGGACCAUAUUUUGUAUCCAAGGAUCCUUAUUUAAAGCUUUCAACAUGUACAGGAAGUUGGAAAUUUUUGGUUUAUGACUUUGUCUAAUAAAGAGAUAGUUCUAAACACAUUCUUGAUCACCAAACAACUUCAGAAAGACAGUGACUGUACAGUUAUCAUUAUCAUCAUCAUCGUCAUCAUCAUAGGUAACAGUUAUAUCAAGCUUAAUAUGUGCUGAACAUUGUUCUGAACACUUUAGGUAGAUGAACUAGAUGUAUGUGAAUAAAAAUUAUUUGGUCCUCACAAAAA